GGGACACGGCCGGGCCGCAGAGCGCGUGUCACCGCCGCCUCUCCUGGGCCACUCCUAACCCCGGAGGAGGGAGGGGAUCGCUCACCUCAGAGUAGCGUUGUCAAGAUUUCGCCUUAGCUGGGGACUCGUUUGCAGAUUUUACACUUGUUUUCUUGUUGACACACGUUAUAUAUGUCAUUAUUGGAAUCUUUGGGUCUGUUCCACCACCAACUUAGUGGGAGCAUCUGUUUUGGCUUAGGCAGCAAAAUGAGCUGGAGGUUUUUCCUUGGAAAAAAAAAUUCUAGCCAAAAAUAUGCCUAUUUUGUUAUUAGGCGUUUAUACUUUUUUUUUUUAACCAAAAACACAUUAUUUGCUUCAAGCGAGUCUGUCAAGCAGUCACCAAUGCUUUCACAGCGGAAAGCAAAACUUUCAGACUUGUCUCUUGUGCAGGAAGUUACAGCACUGUGUUCAACAGGCCACACCAGUGAUCUGUUCAGUAAUUGAGUAACUUUUUUAAAAGAAGCCAAAAUGAAUGUUUUUAGAAACAAAAUUUAAAUAGGACAGUUUUCUAUAGCUCCUCAUUUUUUAGCCAUAAUUGGAGGAGUGUUUAGAUGCAAGGGCCUUGUAAGAUCUAAAAUUUUUUCGAUUUCUCUAAAUCUUCACUCCUUCUAUAAACAUCUGUUGAGCCCUCAUUCUGGACUGGGCCCUGGGUUUACAGUGGCAUGCACAAGGAAACAUGGUCCUCACUUCUGCUGGGGCUUCUAGGUUAGUGGGGAGAAGCAUCUAUGAAAUAUUCGUAUGUAUAGAGGUAAACCUGCACCUGUGGGCUGUGGAAGGGGGCCUGUGGGGCCUGUGAGGUUGUCAGGUGCAACACCAGAAAAGCAUUCUUUGCUGCAAAUCCAUUGCUUUAGAAAGGACCCUCCUGGGUAGUGAUUUGGGAUUUAGAGUAGGUUUGCACAGUGGAGGAGAGCAGUUAGGGUGGCGACUUUUCAUCUACCAGUUGCUAUGAAAGCUUAGGGGGCUGUUGAUAUCACUCGGGUGUAAAGAGAAUUAUUUCAUUGUUCAGUUGGUUGAGUGUAGAUUUUGUUGUAAAAUAUCUUUUUCUCUUUCCUCUUUUUAAAAACAUUGGAGACUAGGAGCUCUCACUGGACUUUGAGCUGCUUGAGACGGGGACUGUGCGAUUCAUCUUUCUGUCUCUAGUUCUUAGCAUGUGCACGGCACAGAGCAGGCGCUCAGAGUGCCUUCAGUGAAGGAAUAAAUGACCAUACCACCAGGCACAGAGUGAGGCCUUUAGAAACCCUGAGCAUCAUCGGGUGCGCCCACCACUUCUGUAUGUGACUCAAAAGAUCGAGGAGCAAAAGGGAGGAAACUGCUAGAGACUGAGAUCAACGCAUACUCUGACAACAGCUUAUUUGGCAAGGAAGCCUCCUGGACUCAGCACCGCAGCCCCUUUGCUGAAGCAACCUGAACAUUGAGAGUGCUUGUGUUUUCUAGCUGCGGUUGGAUUUCUCACGAUGUCCAGUGUUAUCUCCAUGUCUGCCCCUUUCUUCCUGGGGAAGAUCAUUGAUGUCAUCUAUACCAACCCCACUGUGGACUACAGCGACAACCUGACCCGCCUCUGCCUAGGGCUCAGUGCCGUGUUUCUGUGUGGUGCUGCCGCCAAUGCCAUUCGUGUCUACCUCAUGCAAACUUCAGGUCAGCGCAUUGUGAAUAGGCUGAGAACUUCAUUAUUCUCCUCCAUUCUGAGGCAGGAGGUUGCUUUCUUUGACAAGACUCGCACAGGAGAAUUGAUUAACCGCCUCUCAUCAGACACUGCACUCCUGGGGCGCUCAGUGACUGAAAACCUCUCAGAUGGGCUCAGGGCCGGGGCCCAGGCUUCCGUAGGCAUCAGUAUGAUGUUUUUUGUCUCACCUAAUCUGGCCACCUUUGUUUUGAGCGUGGUGCCUCCAGUGUCAAUCAUUGCUGUAAUUUAUGGGCGAUAUCUACGGAAACUGACCAAAGUCACUCAGGAUUCCCUGGCACAAGCCACUCAGCUAGCUGAGGAACGUAUUGGAAAUGUAAGAACUGUUCGAGCUUUUGGGAAAGAAAUGACUGAAAUCGAGAAAUAUGCCAGCAAAGUGGACCAUGUAAUGCAGUUAGCAAGGAAAGAGGCAUUCGCCCGGGCUGGUUUCUUUGGAGCAACUGGGCUCUCCGGAAACCUGAUCGUGCUUUCUGUCCUGUACAAAGGAGGGCUGCUGAUGGGCAGUGCCCACAUGACCGUGGGUGAACUCUCUUCCUUCCUAAUGUAUGCUUUCUGGGUUGGAAUAAGCAUUGGAGGUCUGAGCUCUUUCUACUCGGAGCUGAUGAAAGGACUGGGUGCAGGGGGGCGCCUCUGGGAGCUCCUGGAGAGAGAGCCCAAGCUGCCUUUUAACGAGGGGGUCAUCUUAAAUGAGAAAAGCUUCCAGGGUGCUUUGGAGUUUAAGAACGUGCAUUUUGCCUAUCCAGCUCGCCCAGAGGUGCCCAUAUUUCAGGAUUUCAGCCUUUCCAUUCCGUCAGGAUCUGUCACGGCACUGGUUGGCCCAAGUGGUUCUGGCAAAUCAACAGUGCUUUCACUCCUGCUGAGGUUGUACGACCCUGCUUCUGGAACUAUUAGUCUUGAUGGCCAUGACAUCCGUCAGCUAAACCCAGUGUGGCUGAGAUCCAAAAUUGGGACAGUGAGUCAGGAACCCAUUUUGUUUUCUUGCUCUAUUGCUGAGAACAUUGCUUAUGGUGCUGAUGACCCUUCCUCUGUGACCGCUGAGGAAAUCCAGAGAGUGGCUGAAGUGGCCAAUGCAGUGGCCUUCAUCCGGAAUUUCCCCCAAGGGUUCAACACUGUGGUUGGAGAAAAGGGUGUUCUCCUCUCAGGUGGGCAGAAACAGCGGAUUGCGAUUGCCCGUGCUCUGCUAAAGAAUCCCAAAAUUCUUCUCCUAGAUGAAGCAACCAGUGCGCUGGAUGCCGAAAAUGAGUACCUUGUUCAAGAAGCUCUAGAUCGACUGAUGGAUGGAAGAACGGUGUUAGUUAUUGCCCAUCGUCUGUCCACCAUUAAGAAUGCUAAUAUGGUUGCUGUUCUUGACCAAGGAAAAAUUACUGAAUAUGGAAAACAUGAAGAGCUGCUUUCAAAACCAAAUGGGAUAUACAGAAAACUAAUGAACAAACAAAGUUUUAUUUCAGCAUAAGGAAGCAAUUACUGGUAAACAAUAUGAGACUUUAAUGCAAAACAGUGUUGCAGAAAAAAAACUCAGAGACUAUGAAAUACAUAAACCAUAUAUCAAGUUAUUUGAAAAAUACCUAUUUUUUUCCAAAGUGUGUAAAAGAUUGUUUUGAAACGUACCUGUUCUCAAGAUCUUUUUAUUCAGAGUUUUAAUAAUUGUAACUUUUUAAAUGUCUAUAGCACUGAAGUUAUUUUCAGGUUUUGUAUUUUCUUUUCUUGUGGAAUAUUUUAAUUAAUAUAGCAUGGCACCUCAUUUUCUUUUGCCUGCUGUUAAAGAUUGAAGCUAUUGUCAAAUGACAACUUUAAAAAGGCAAUUAUAAAUAAAAAGCCUGAUUAUUUUAGGCCAGUUUACCAAUCACUGUGUAAUUCUUCUGGUAGUAUUCUACCUACUUUUAAGUCUAAUUUUACAGAUAGAAUAAUGGAAAUUGAAAAUUUAACCCUUUAUUCCGAUAAUCUCAUGAAGCAAACCUAACUAUUUAACAUCAGCUGGAAAGAAGGGAACAUUUAUAUUGCCCAUCUCCUGUGUCUUCAAAGGUGUGAGAGCUGAGGAAUAUGUGUUCCUAUGGGAACUAUGUUUGAAUAUGUGCAGUUUUCAACAUUUUGGCACAUGAAAGCCUGACAAGUUUUUAAAAGGGCAGAAGCUUUAUUUUUUGAACAGGAAAACAUGUUUUUUAAAUUCACAUGUUUGUAUGAGUACUUUUGCGAAGCAAGGCAUGAACUGCUAGGUAUUAUUAAGAAUGAAUGAUUUUUGCAUUUAAGUUGUUUGAAGGCAUGUAUUUUGAAAAAUAUCUGUUACAAAUUUAUAAUUUCAAGACAAAUUGAAUCUUAUUUUAUAAUACUUUUGGAAUUUCAUUAAUAAGGCUAAAAUUUGAGGAAUAUAACUAAUUUUCAGCCUUAAGACAUUUAAGUUUGGAAGUCCUUGCUAUUCAACAGAAUAACAAGAAAACUUCAGAAUGUAUCACUCUCCUGAAAAGAAGAUAUUAAUAAGCCCUUUUAUUUAUGGUUAUAGUUUUAUUUAUAGUCUCAAAAUUCCUAAAGCAAUGCUACAACCAUUGAAUUUGCCAUAUUUUGUAUCAGUGCUGUUAAUUUGCUGUUGCCUCAAGAAAAAGUGCUUUUUCUCCAUGGAUGAGGCUAGACCCUAAGAAGUAAUUAAGUCAAUGUAAAUCAAAUGGAAGUUUUCCCAUGAACUAAGCAUUUAUUAGUUCCCUGAUUAGACUGGAAGAAGAAACCACUAUUUCAUGAAAAGCAUGGAAUAUUAUAUUUUAUUGUUCAUAAUUAAUGAAUAAAAUUGAUAUGAAUGAAUAUAGUGUUCUUUGAAUUAGUAAACAGUACAUCUGUGACAAUCAUUUUUAACAAGCUCUACUUGUGUUCUUUAUAAAGUGUGAUUUUCAGAAAGCAAACAACACAAUUACAAGGUUGAAUCUGAGGAAAAUAAUCCUUGUGCCAUAGAAGUAUUUACGAAAUUGCAUUUCAUUGUUAUGUUUUAUUUUCUGAUACAUGAUGUUCAAUUUUAUCUUUAGGUAAUAUUUUAUAUCAUAGAUUAAAAUUUAUAGUGAACUUUA